GUCACUGUCCGCCGCCGUGUCCGCGGCUGCGCCAGACAGUGUAGAACCUGCGGCCUCGAUGUCCUUCUCCCGUGCCCUAUUGUGGGCUCGGCUCCCGGCGGGGCGCCAGGCUGGCCACCGGGCAGCCAUCUGCUCUGCCCUUCGUCCCCACUUUGGGCCCUUUCCCGGGGUUCUGGGGCAAGUUUCUGUCCUUGCCACCGCCUCCUCCUCUGCCUCCGGUGGCUCCAAAAUACCAAACACGUCCUUGUUCGUGCCCCUGACUGUGAAACCUCAGGGCCCCAGCGCCGACGGCGACGUCGGGGCCGAGCUAACCCGGCCUCUGGACAAGACUAUUCCAAUUCACCUGAAAAUGUAAAUGUCUUUGCUGCUUCCUGUAAGAAGAUAGAAUAAAGACAUGGGUUUGUCAGCACUAGAUUUUCUUCUGGUGGAGAAUCCUUAGAUACUUCAUUGGGUCUGUGUGCCAGAUGAAGUAAAGAAGGUCUUAGACAAAUUUUACAAGAGGAAAGAAAUUCAGAAACUGGGUGCUGAUUAUGGACUUGAUGCUCGUCUCUUCCACCAAGCUUUCAUAAGCUUUAGAAAUUAUAUUAUGCAGUCUCAUUCCCUGGAUGUGGACAUUCACAUUGUUUUGAAUGAUAUUUGCUUCGGUGCAGGCUCUGGAGUGCAGUGGCUCAGUCUCAGCUCAGUGUGUAGCCUCAACCUCCUGGGCUCAAGCCAUCCUUCCAGCUCAUGCGGAUGAUUUAUUCCCAUUUUUCUUGAGACAUGCCAAACAAAUAUUUCCUGUGUUGGACUGUAAGGAUGAUCUACGUAAAAUCAGUGACUUAAGAAUACCACCUAACUGGUACCCAGAUGCUAGAGCCAUGCAGCGGAAGAUAAUAUUUCAUUCAGGCCCCACAAACAGUGGAAAGACUUAUCACGCAAUCCAGAAAUACUUCUCAGCAAAGUCUGGAGUGUAUUGUGGCCCUCUAAAAUUACUGGCACAUGAGAUCUUCGAAAAGAGUAAUGCUGCUGGUGUGCCAUGUGACUUGGUGACAGGUGAAGAGCGUGUGACAGUUCAGCCAAAUGGGAAACAGGCUUCACAUGUUUCUUGUACAGUUGAGAUGUGCAGUGUUACAACUCCUUAUGAAGUGGCUGUAAUUGAUGAAAUUCAAAUGAUUAGAGAUCCAGCCAGAGGAUGGGCCUGGACCAGAGCACUUCUAGGACUGUGUGCUGAAGAGGUUCAUUUGUGUGGAGAACCUGCUGCUAUUGACCUGGUGAUGGAGCUUAUGUACACAACGGGGGAGGAAGUGGAGGUUCGAGACUAUAAGAGGCUUACCCCCAUUUCUGUGCUGGACCAUGCACUAGAAUCUUUAGAUAACCUUCGGCCUGGGGACUGCAUUGUCUGUUUUAGCAAGAAUGAUAUUUAUUCUGUGAGUCGGCAGAUUGAAAUUCGGGGAUUAGAAUCAGCUGUUAUAUAUGGCAGUCUCCCACCUGGGACCAAACUUGCUCAAGCAAAAAAGUUUAAUGAUCCCAAUGACCCAUGCAAAAUCUUGGUUGCUACAGAUGCAAUUGGCAUGGGACUUAAUUUGAGCAUAAGGAGAAUUAUUUUUUACUCCCUUAUAAAGCCCAGUAUCAAUGAAAAGGGAGAGAGAGAACUAGAACCAAUCACAACCUCUCAAGCCCUGCAGAUUGCUGGCAGAGCUGGCAGAUUCAGCUCACGGUUUAAAGAAGGAGAGGUUACAACAAUGAAUCAUGAAGAUCUCAGUUUAUUAAAGGAAAUUUUGAAGAGGCCUGUGGAUCCUAUAAGGGCAGCUGGUCUUCAUCCAACUGCUGAGCAGAUUGAAAUGUUUGCCUACCAUCUCCCUGAUGCAACACUGUCCAAUCUCAUUGAUAUUUUUGUAGACUUUUCACAAGUUGAUGGGCAGUAUUUUGUCUGCAAUAUGGAUGAUUUUAAAUUUUCUGCAGAGUUGAUCCAGCAUAUUCCACUAAGUCUGCGAGUGAGGUAUGUUUUCUGCACAGCUCCUAUCAACAAGAAGCAGCCUUUUGUGUGUUCUUCACUGUUACAGUUUGCCAGGCAGUAUAGCAGGAAUGAGCCCCUGACCUUUGCAUGGUUACGCCGAUACAUCAAAUGGCCUUUACUUCCACCUAAGAAUAUUAAAGACCUCAUGGAUCUUGAAGCUGUCCACGAUGUCUUGGAUCUUUACUUGUGGCUAAGCUACCGAUUUAUGGAUAUGUUUCCAGAUGCCAGCCUUAUUCGAGAUCUCCAGAAAGAACUAGAUGGUAUUAUCCAAGAUGGUGUGCACAAUAUCACUAAAUUGAUUAAAAUGUCUGAGACGCAUAAGCUGUUGAAUUUGGAGGGCUUUCCAUCAGGGAGCCAGUCACGAUUGUCAGGAACCUUAAAGAGCCAAGCUAGAAGGACACGCGGCACCAAAGCUCUAGGGAGUAAAGCUACUGAGCCACCCAGCCCCGAUGCAGGAGAGCUGUCCCUUGCUUCCAGAUUGGUGCAGCAAGGACUCCUCACUCCAGACAUGCUGAAACAGCUAGAAAAAGAGUGGAUGACACAACAAACUGAACACAACAAAGAAAAAACAGAGUCUGGGACUCAUCCAAAAGGGACGAGAAGAAAGAAGAAGGAACCUGAUUCGGACUAGUUUUCUGUUCCUGUUUUUUUUUUUUUAUUUAAUUUUGCAAAUAAAAAUUUAUUUUGAA